UGUGUCUCUGUGUGUGAGAGAGCGAGCGAGCGUGUAUGUUCUCAUUAGGGGACGAUCUAUGAUUUGACAGCCUCACUGCUGCUGCUCCUGCUGCUGCUUCUGCUUCUGCCGCGGCUGUAUGGUUUGUCAUUAGUUGGAAAGGGCUGUGAGGGUUUGGAGAAACUGCAGUUUUAAAGACUGAGCACUGCUAAGUGGUCUCCCUCUCAAAUAGAGUAGACAAGAUUUUCUGCAAGAUUAGAAACUUGGAACUAUUACCACUUCAUCUACCCAGAAAAUCAGGCAGCGCUACAGAGGAUAAGGGGGAUGGAACUGCUGCAAUAAAGGUGGGCGCUGGAAAGAAGAUGUUUUGAGAAGUCAGUGUUUCCGAGAAACUUUAAGCUUCUAAAGAUGGAAAACGAGACAGUCAGUGAACUGAACCAAACACAGCUUCAGCCACGAGCAGUGGUGGCCUUAGAAUACCAGGUGGUCACCAUCUUACUUGUACUCAUUAUUUGUGGCCUGGGCAUUGUAGGCAACAUCAUGGUAGUCCUGGUUGUCAUGAGAACCAAGCACAUGAGGACCCCCACAAACUGCUACCUGGUGAGCCUGGCAGUAGCUGAUCUCAUGGUCUUGGUGGCCGCAGGCCUCCCCAACAUAACAGACAGUAUCUACGGUUCCUGGGUCUAUGGCUAUGUUGGAUGCCUCUGCAUUACUUACCUCCAGUAUUUGGGAAUUAAUGCAUCCUCUUGUUCAAUAACAGCCUUUACCAUUGAGAGGUACAUAGCAAUCUGUCACCCCAUCAAAGCCCAGUUUCUCUGCACAUUUUCCAGAGCCAAAAAGAUUAUCAUCUUUGUCUGGGCUUUCACAUCUCUUUACUGUAUGCUCUGGUUCUUCUUGCUGGAUCUCAAUAUUAGCACCUACAAAGAUGCUAUUGUGAUAUCCUGUGGCUACAAGAUCUCCAGGAAUUACUACUCACCUAUUUACCUAAUGGACUUUGGUGUCUUUUAUGUUGUGCCAAUGAUCCUGGCUACCGUCCUCUAUGGAUUCAUAGCUAGAAUCCUUUUCUUAAAUCCCAUUCCUUCAGAUCCUAAAGAAAACUCUAAGACAUGGAAAAAUGAUUCAACCCAUCAGAACACAAAUCUGAAUGUAAAUACCUCUAAUAGAUGUUUCAACAGCACAGUAUCUUCAAGGAAGCAGGUCACCAAGAUGCUGGCAGUGGUUGUAAUUCUGUUUGCCCUUUUAUGGAUGCCCUACAGGACUCUAGUGGUUGUCAACUCAUUUCUCUCCAGUCCUUUCCAAGAAAAUUGGUUUUUGCUCUUUUGCAGAAUUUGCAUUUAUCUCAACAGUGCCAUCAACCCGGUGAUUUACAAUCUCAUGUCCCAGAAAUUCCGUGCAGCCUUCAGAAAGCUCUGCAACUGCAAGCAGAAGCCAACAGAGAAACCUGCUAACUACAGUGUGGCCCUAAAUUACAGCGUCAUCAAGGAGUCAGACCAUUUCAGCACAGAGCUUGAUGAUAUCACUGUCACUGACACUUACCUGUCUGCCACAAAAGUGUCUUUUGAUGACACCUGCUUGGCUUCUGAGGUAUCCUUUAGCCAAAGUUGAUUCAUGAAUUAGAAGAAAAUGGAUGACAAAGAAAAUGAGAAUCUGUGCAGUCAUCAACAAAAGGGAGAACAUGGCCAAUAGUCAUAUGUGAAGACAGAGCAGAUCAGUCUUUGUCAAUGCUCUAACAAAUUCUGGCCCUAGAUACUUUAACCCAUGAGGAUGAUUCAGACUUUCCUUCUUACAAACUAAUAUCACUAAAAAUGGAGCAGAUCUGUGAAAUAGCUAAAUGAUGGAAACUUAAAGUUUAGCCCUUUUCAUUUAACUUAAGAAAUUCACUAUAUUUUCUGGACUUAUAGAGUUUCAAUAAAAUCUAGACAUCAAUUUACAUUAUUCAUAGUAACCUUAUCAAAUGUCACUUUUCAACUUCCCUAAUUUAUUUAUACAUUCGAUAAUUUGACAACAUGCAGAUUUUUAAAUGUUUGCAUUUAGUAUUCAUUUUAACAUAGUACAGGGCUAGUUCAUGAAUAUCUGAAAUUAAAGGGAAAAAUAUUACAGAAACAUUUUAUUUAUUGAGUAAAAAUAAGAUUUUAGACAUACAUGUUAACUGUAUUUUAAAAGUUGCCAUAAUGUUUAUAAAAUUCUGAGAUGAUUUUUAUAUCUUAGAAGGUAGAUAAUCAUCACUCAACUUUAAUGUAAAAUAAACCUCAAAAUAUCUGAAAUUAUUAAUUAAGGAGAAAUGUAGAUUUUAAGAUAAAUCCAACUCUUAUCAACUCUUCCAGCCUCCCACAUGAUGGGUGGAAAAAGGCAAAAGCCCAGAUUAAGUAACUGUGAAGAUACAAACUAACAUACAAUUAAAUUUGAAAAGUAUAGUCAAGACAAAGCAAGUAUUUAUAAUUAGAUUUUGCUUCUUCUCUGACGCUUUUAAGCAAUAAAAUCUUUUUGAACAUUCUUGUUUAUAAACUACUCAGCCAUGUCAAGCAAAUCAUUCAAGCAAAAUCUAGCUGAAAAGUCUGAAACAUUCUUAAAAGCUUUGUUGUUAUUCUAAGUCAGCCAAAAUCCUGGUAUCCCUCUUCCAGAUAAAGAGCUCCCACUGAGAAUUGUAGUCUAUGGAUUUUACCUUGACUGCAAUUGUCUUUCCUUCCUAUCUGCUUGUUGUUUGUAGGUUCUUUUUUUGUUUUUCUCAAAUGCUAGUGAUAUUUUGUUUACAGAUUCUAAAAGCAAUGCAAAAUUCUGUUGGCUUUAUUUUCAGCAGAGUUAAAACUGAUUUCAUCAUAUUAUCAGUAUGUCAUCUUUAUAUUUAUGACUGACAUCUGCUAUUCCAGUGUUUAUUGGAGACUUGUGAAUGAAUCUGUCCAGGACACUUGUCAGUUCCUACCUGAAUCUCUUACCUAUUGAGAUUUGGCCAACCAGAAUCUCCGAGGGCAAAAAUUGCCCUUGGUGAUGGUUCAGUAGUCAUUGAUUUUUAAUGAGUAGAUCAAAAAAGUACCCAUACCUUUACAUGCCCGUAGGCUGUCAUUUUCCCUCUCCAGCCUAUAUCCCUAUUUUAUGGACUUUUCUAGAACCUAAUCGCUAAUGAUAAUUAUGCCUCCCCAUCUUCUUAAUGAAGAAUAUACCAUUCUUCUGAAACUUGUUUUUACGUGCUGUUUCAUGGAGACUAUGCUAUCCAGAACCUCAUUCUAGAGUGCGCUUUUUUUUUUUUGAAAAUUGGCCUUAUCUACUCCAGCAAGACAUUUUUAUCCUGUUACUAUAACAGUAAAUGAAUGCAAGCAAAUAUUUGCAGGAAAUACCCUAAAACCCUACCUGCAUGACAGUAAGCAAUCUAUGUUAACUGACUUUUCAUUCUGGUAUAAAUAUUAAUCUUGGCAUCAUAUAAAUAGAGCACCAGAGUGACCCAACCCCAAAUCACACAAGCACAUGUGUGUUUAUAAACACAUACCCACAUGUUCAUAAAUUGGUGAAAAAGGGGAUUGGAAUAUACGAGAUUUUUUCAUUACAGAAAGGACCUAAUAUCAUUGAGCAUCGACUAUGUCUCAGGUAUGCUGGUAGGUAGUCAAUCAACAUUAUCUUCAUCACAAUUUCACUACAGCUGUAAUUUCUCUGAUGAUUAGACCAGUAUUCCUGUGACCUAAUUCCUAAUUAAUAAAAAGUUAUGGAUUUUGCAGAAUGAUUA